AAUUCCGGAAGGUGCUGCACAGCUGUGGCGGCGGGUACUGCGUUAGUGAUUAGAGUUUCUUCCCUGCCGGAGGUGGGAUACACGGUAGCAUCAUGGUCGAGGAGGUACAGAAACAUUCUGUACACACCCUUGUGUUCAGGUCGUUGAAGAGGACCCAUGACAUGUUUGUAGCUGAUAAUGGAAAACCUGUGCCUUUAGAUGAAGAGAGUCACAAACGAAAAAUGGCAAUCAAGCUUCGUAAUGAGUAUGGUCCUGUGUUGCAUAUGCCUACUUCAAAAGAAAAUCUUAAAGAGAAGGGUCCUCAGAAUGCAACGGAUUCAUAUGUUCAUAAACAGUACCCUGCCAAUCAAGGACAAGAAGUUGAAUACUUUGUGGCAGGUACACAUCCAUACCCACCAGGACCUGGGGUUGCUUUGACAGCAGAUACUAAGAUCCAGAGAAUGCCAAGUGAAUCAGCUGCACAGUCCUUAGCGGUGGCAUUACCUUUGCAGACCAAGGCUGAUGCAAAUCGUACUGCCCCUAGUGGAAGUGAAUACCGACAUCCUGGGGCUUCUGACCGUCCACAGCCUACAGCGAUGAAUUCAAUUGUCAUGGAGACUGGCAAUACCAAGAACUCUGCACUGAUGGCUAAAAAAGCCCCUACAAUGCCAAAACCCCAGUGGCACCCACCGUGGAAACUCUACAGGGUUAUCAGUGGGCAUCUUGGCUGGGUUCGAUGUAUUGCUGUGGAACCUGGAAAUCAGUGGUUUGUUACUGGAUCUGCUGACAGAACUAUAAAGAUCUGGGACUUGGCUAGUGGCAAAUUAAAACUGUCAUUGACUGGGCAUAUUAGUACUGUGCGGGGCGUGAUAGUAAGCACAAGGAGCCCAUAUCUGUUCUCUUGUGGAGAAGACAAACAAGUGAAAUGCUGGGAUCUCGAAUACAAUAAGGUUAUACGGCAUUAUCAUGGACAUUUAAGUGCAGUGUAUGGUUUGGAUUUGCACCCGACAAUCGAUGUGUUGGUAACCUGUAGUCGAGAUUCAACUGCACGGAUUUGGGAUGUGAGAACUAAAGCCAGUGUACACACAUUAUCUGGACAUACAAAUGCAGUUGCUACAGUGAGAUGUCAGGCUGCAGAACCACAAAUUAUUACAGGAAGCCAUGAUACUACAAUUCGAUUAUGGGAUCUGGUGGCUGGAAAAACAAGAGUGACAUUAACAAAUCACAAAAAAUCAGUUAGGGCUGUGGUUUUACAUCCAAGACAUUACACAUUUGCAUCUGGUUCUCCAGAUAACAUAAAGCAGUGGAAAUUCCCUGAUGGAAGUUUCAUUCAAAAUCUUUCCGGUCAUAAUGCUAUUAUUAACACAUUGACGGUAAAUUCUGAUGGAGUGCUUGUAUCUGGAGCUGACAAUGGCACCAUGCAUCUUUGGGACUGGAGAACUGGCUACAAUUUUCAGAGAGUUCACGCAGCUGUGCAACCUGGGUCUUUGGACAGUGAAUCAGGAAUAUUUGCUUGUGCUUUUGAUCAGUCUGAAAGUCGAUUACUAACAGCUGAAGCUGAUAAAACCAUUAAAGUAUACAGAGAGGAUGACACAGCCACAGAAGAAACUCAUCCAGUCAGCUGGAAACCAGAAAUUAUCAAGAGAAAGAGAUUUUAAUGAAUGUGGAAUUUUUUCUCUCUCUUUUUUUUUCUUUUUAAUUAAAAAAAAAAAAGCUUGGCGUUCAUGAGGAUAUCCAGUCAUUUUGUGCUCUGGCUGGGAAUAUAAAGGAGAAAUUCACUUGCUUCAAUCAUUGCUGCUUCAUAUUUUACAAUAAACUGUCCCCUGUCCCCUACCCCUGUGUUUUUAUUUCUAAAACAAUUUGUGAUACUAGGAAGAUGCAGAUAUCAAGUAAAUGCAGGUUUAUUGAACAUAACUAUUCUAGAUGUAAUAUUUUGACAGUCUUAUUAGAAAACCCCCUUUUUUAAAAAAAAUGUAUGAAACCGAUAAUUAGGACAUUUGAAGGAGCAGUAGUUUUUUUUUAGUCCUUUAAAAAAUAACAUCUGUGACUAAUAAUUUGAGAUUAAAAGAUUUGAAGUCUUAAUUUAUGUAUGUUUAUUCCAAAAACAGUUUUUGAGUGUAUGUUCUACAAAGUUCUGCACUAGAUACUGUUCAGGAAAUAGACAAGUAAGAUGUGUCUAUCCUCUAAGACUUCCAGUUUGGUAGCUUAGUAUAGAAAUUCUGUAACAGAGGUGCAGGUGAAAUGCUGGGGGAACAGAAGGGAUAAGACCAUUUAUUUUUCUCAGGAAGGAUUGUGGAAGACUUCAUAGAGUAAGUGGCAUUGGAGAUUACCUUGAAGUGAAGGAAGACAAAGAAGGAAAAGAGAUGAGGCAUAAAGUGAUGAAACCAGGCACAAGAAAGUGUGCGGUGUGUUCUGGGACAAAGAAUGUUCUGCUACUGUCGAAUAAUGGGACUAAAGCUGGCUUGUUCUGGGGAAAGCUCAUAUAAGUAUGGAUUUUAUUCCUCAACUAGUAGGAUACCAAUACUGGUAUUGAAACUUGGGGAAAAUAACUGGAGAUACCAGUGCAGCUAUUUAAAGCUGUAGCAAGGGCUGCAAUCUUGCGGAGAUUUUAAAGAGAAGUUUUAAAGUUUCUAAUACUGAUGCCUCUUUUUGGUAAAUACAAGUUUUAUAAAUCCUGCCCUGGGAUCCUGAUUCCCCAUUAAUCAAGAUUUGUCAGACUUCACCUUCUAUAAUUAGAAAACACAGUUAUAAGAACAGUCAAUUUUUUAAAUUUUCCAAAUUAAAAAAUUGCACCAUGAUUUUGAACAAGCACUUCCAAUUACAUUACCCAUCUUGUAUGCCAUAGGUGGGAGUAUAAUUGUCACAGCCUUUAGGAAUGUAGUUUUCUGGGAUUUAUUGAAACUUUGAACCUUUUGGCCUACUAAGUUCAUUCCUAGGAAACUGCCUAAUGGGAAUGAUCUGACAAGUGUACACAAGCAAAGUCAUUGCACCUUUGUUCUUUAAUACUUAAAACUAGCCCAAAUGCCCUGUCAGUAAGGGACUGGUUUAAUAGAUGGUACCUUUAUGCAAUUUGUUUCUAAGUAUUCGUUAAGAGAGUGAGGAAUGUCUGGAUUAUUAGGGCAAGAUUUCUAAACUUGGGUAAAAAAAAAAGUUGUGCAAGCAUUUUUGUGGACAACUUGAUGCUCUAAAAUAUAAGUAACACCACAUUACUAACAGUGGCUUUGUUAGGAAGCAGAAUUAUGGAAGAACUUUCAUGGGUGGCUUUACAUAUUUCUAUAAUGUUUUAAUUUUCUAUAAGCAUGUAUUUCGUAAACUUAAAUAAAGAAAAAAGAACACUA